CAGGUCUGGUUCCAGAACCGCAGAGCUAAGCAACGGAAGCAAGAGCGCUCACUGCUUCAGCCUCUGGCCCAUCUGUCUCCUGCCGCCUUUUCCAGCUUCUUGCCAGAGUCCACUGCUUGCCCCUAUUCUUACGCAGCACCACCACCACCAGUGACCUGCUUCCCUCACCCCUACAGCCAUGCCCUCCCUUCCCAGCCCUCCACAGGAGGCGCCUUUGCUUUGUCACACCAGUCUGAGGACUGGUACCCUACCUUGCACCCAGCCCCUGCCGGCCAUCUGCCCUGCCCCCCACCCCCUCCCAUGCUCCCCCUCAGCCUUGAGCCAUCCAAGUCCUGGAACUGAGGUCAAACAAGUACCACCAAGGUGAUCCCCAGCCUGCGGCCCUCGUGAAAAGACAAGAAAAUGGGGUGGCUUCCUUUCCAUCUAUGGGUGAAGCAGAUGCAUGGUGAGGGUCAGCUCAGCGAUUAGAAAUUUAAAAAUGGGAGAUCAUGGUGAAUUCUCACUGGGGUGAUUAGUGGAGGAAGUCUGGGGAGGUGAGCUACUGGAAGAGACAGGGCAAGAUGCCUCGGUGGAGCUGCCUGCUGAAGGGUGAUAUUGAUGAAGACAGUUGCUGGUGAGUGGAGAUGAUUGAAGGGCUAGGAGGUGAGGGCCUUCAUUAAUUGAGAUCACGAUUGAAGAAGAUCCCAGCUCUUUCUGGCUGAUUUCAGUAAGGCUUCUGACUUAAGAGUCUACCUAUACAUCCCUUCCCCAUUGCCCACCCCGCCAUCUCAAUCAGUCACUGACUUUUGUUUAUUCUGUCCUAGAAAUACCUUUUUU